GAAUGUGGCGGCGGUAGUUCCAGGCGACGGCGGACGGUGGUACGGUCCUGGAGGGCCCAGUGCGCGGGGCUAGCCGUGGCUGGAGAGCUUCGAAGAGCCUUGAAAUGUGAGGAGGAGGAAGAUAGCUGUUGCAGAAGUAGUGGCCAAGGUAUCGUUCUGGACGCGCCUGCGGCAGGAGGGUCGCCGCGUCCACUUCCGCCAGCCCCACCUCCCCCCGGCCUUCCUGGAGUCCCUGAAAGAGGAAGAAGUAGGUUUUAAGGUGCGAAACAAGGGCGUAGUGAUCCCUGUUUGACUUCCCUUCGGUUUUCAGUAUCAUUCUAAAUUCGGUGGCCGAAAGCUCGGGCCGUGGAGUCCCACUCGCCGCGCUUUUCGCCGUUCAGCCACUCGAUCUGCGCUUUCAGAUGUUCCGGCUUCCAUGGAGACCCUAAUUUCCUACUUUGCAAAAUUGUGUAGAUUAAGUGAUGUGCAAAUAAAGCUUUUACAAUAGCUAAAAGCCUGGCUCAACGUAAGGACACAAGAAAAUUGACAGCAGUUCUUUGUGCAGCGUGAUACCGUUGACGUCCUCCUUGUCCAGGCCAUUCUCUUCCUCACUUACCCUGGAGAGGCCGGCACUGACUAGUAUCCUACCUGGCUGUCUUCGCAGCAGGACUAAUUGGAGAAUUAUGGACGGAGAUCAAAUAUGCUAGGUUCUUUAAAUCCAGAGCGCUUACACGAGUACUGUACAGAUUGAGACCGUCAUCUCGCGCUGUGGUCUGUCUUUGCUUUCAUCCCUUCUGUCUACCACACCCCCUGCUAAUAACCAUCGCCUUAUUUAGACAGGAUAUAAAACUUUUGAUAUGGCAAGUUUCUUUUGUGAUUUUUAACUUGAUUAAAAGUAAUAACGAAAGCUUUUUAGGCAAAAGAUGGCCAAGGAAAGAUGCCUGAAAAAGUCCUUUCAAGAUAGUCUUGAAGACAUAAAGAAGCGAAUGAAAGAGAAAAGGAAUAAAAACUUGGCAGAGAUUGGCAAACGCAGGUCUUUUAUAGCUGCACCAUGCCAAAUAAUCACCAACACUUCUACACUGCUGAAAAAUUACCAAGACAACAACAAAAUGUUAGUUUUAGCUUUGGAAAAUGAAAAAUCCAAAGUGAAAGAAGCCCAAGAUAUCAUCCUACAGCUGAGAAAAGAAUGUUACUAUCUCACAUGUCAGCUAUAUGCAUUGAAAGGAAAACUUACAUCACAACAAACAGUAGAACCUGCUCAGAACCAGGAAAUAUGUUCCUCUGGAAUGGACCCCAAUAGUGAUGACAGCUCCAGAAAUUUAUUUGUGAAGGAUUUACCGCAAAUUCCUCUUGAAGAAACUGAACUUCCAGGACAAGGAGAAUCAUUUCAAAUAGAAGAUCAGAUACCUACUAUUCCUCAAGACACACUGGGAGUUGAUUUUGAUUCAGGUGAAGCUAAGUCUACUGAUAAUGUCUUACCUAGAACUGUAUCUGUUCGUAGCAGUUUAAAGAAACAUUGUAACAGUAUAUGUCAGUUUGAUAGCUUGGAUGAUUUUGAAACCAGUCAUUUGGCAGGGAAGUCUUUUGAAUUCGAAAGAGUUGGAUUUUUAGACCCACUAGUAAACAUGCACAUACCUGAAAAUGUACAACACAAUGCUUGUCAAUGGAGCAAGGACCAAGUUAACUUAUCACCAAAGCUGAUUCAGCCAGGAACGUUUACUAAAACAAAAGAAGACAUUUUAGAAUCUAAAUCUGAACAAACUAAAAGUAAGCAAAGAGAUACACAAGAAAGAAAAAGAGAAGAGAAAAGAAAAGCUAACAGGAGAAAAUCAAAACGUAUGUCAAAAUAUAAAGAGAAUAAAAGCGAAAAUAAAAAAACUGUUCCCCAAAAAAAAAUGCACAAAUCUGUCAGUUCCAAUGAUGCUUACAAUUUUAAUUUGGAAGAGGGUGUUCAUCUUACUCCUUUCCGACAAAAAGUGAGCAAUGACUCUAAUAGAGAAGAAAACAACGAGUCUGAAGUGAGCCUCUGUGAAUCAAGUGGUUCAGGAGAUGAUUCCGAUGACCUCUAUUUGCCCACUUGCAAGUACAUUCAGAAUCCCACGAGCAAUUCAGAUAGACCAGUCACCAGGCCUCUAGCUAAAAGAGCACUGAAAUACACAGAUGAAAAAGAGACGGAGGGUUCUAAGCCAACAAAAACUCCUACCACUACACCACCUGAAACUCAGCAGUCACCUCAUCUUAGCCUGAAGGAUAUCACCAAUGUCUCCUUGUAUCCUGUUGUGAAAAUCAGAAGACUUUCUCUUUCUCCAAAAAAGAAUAAAGCAAGCCCAGCAGUGGCUCUGCCUAAACGUAGGUGCACAGCCAGCGUGAACUAUAAGGAGCCCACCCUCGCUUCGAAACUGAGAAGAGGGGACCCUUUUACAGAUUUGUGUUUUUUGAAUUCUCCUAUUUUCAAGCAGAAAAAGGAUUUGAGACGUUCUAAAAAAAGAGCCCUGGAGGUAUCACCUGCCAAAGAAGCAAUUUUUAUUUUAUAUUAUGUUCGAGAAUUUGUUUCGAGAUUCCCAGACUGUAGGAAAUGUAAACUUGAAACCCACAUCUGCUUGAGGUAAAGUCCACGGGCUUCACAUCCUUAGAAAACUUUUUUAGUCCAUGCAUUCACUAAUGUAUGCAGACCUUUAAUAGAUUCUAGCUUUAUGUGUUGGGGGAGAGAUGGAGGGGUGUUGACAGUCUGUUUCACUCAGCCUACAUACAUAAUAAAAUCUAAGCCCUUUAAUUAGAGAUAGCAACUUUCCCAGGGUGACCGAGGAAUCAGUACGUGUUGAACCCCUCUUUUAAGUUUCCUUUUGGUUGUGUCACUUGGAGAUUGCCUUUUCUUUCUUGUAAGCUCAGCUGUGUCCUCAAAUAUAUUGCAUUUUACCCAGCAUUUCCAGGUGUUUUCAGGGGUCAAAGUUUUUAAGUUAUCUUAGUCUUUGAUAUUGUGUAAGCGAAAUUCUCCAAUCCCAUCUCCUAGAUGAUUUUUUUUUAAAUCACAAAAUGUGAUUAUGCUUAACAGCUGUUUCCUGUUUCUCUUAAAAUAAAAUCCAUUUCCUAUUUCUCUUAAAAUAAAAUCCAUUAUUCUUAA